AGUGGGUGUUGGAGGCUUUAAGGUAGCUUUAAAUUCGUGUUGUCCUGGGAGCUCGCCCUUUUCGGCUGGAGUCGGGCUUUACGGCGCCGGAUGGCUCUGGACGUGAAGUCUCGGGCAAAGCGUUAUGAGAAGCUGGACUUCCUUGGGGAGGGACAGUUUGCCACCGUUUACAAGGCCAGAGAUAAGAACACCAACCAAAUUGUCGCCAUUAAGAAAGAGUCUCUGCUGGUAGCCACUACAGCUGUGAAUGUGCUGUGUCAUACCUGAAGCCAAUAUGUCUCGGAGUUUCACCUGAGGCCCAUGAUCAAACUUGGACAUAGAUCAGAAGCUAAAGAUGGUAUAAAUAGAACCGCCUUAAGAGAGAUAAAAUUAUUACAGGAGCUAAGUCAUCCAAAUAUAAUUGGUCUCCUUGAUGCUUUUGGACAUAAAUCUAAUAUUAGCCUUGUCUUUGAUUUUAUGGAAACUGAUCUAGAGGUUAUAAUAAAGGAUAAUAGUCUUGUGCUGACACCAUCACACAUCAAAGCCUACAUGUUGAUGACUCUUCAAGGAUUAGAAUAUUUACAUCAACAUUGGAUCCUACAUAGGGAUCUGAAACCAAACAACUUGUUGCUAGAUGAAAAUGGAGUUCUAAAACUGGCAGAUUUUGGCCUGGCCAAAUCUUUUGGGAGCCCCAAUAGAGCUUAUACACAUCAGGUUGUAACCAGGUGGUAUCGGGCCCCCGAGUUACUAUUUGGAGCUAGGAUGUAUGGUGUAGGUGUGGACAUGUGGGCUGUUGGCUGUAUAUUAGCAGAGUUACUUCUAAGGGUUCCUUUUUUGCCAGGAGAUUCAGACCUUGAUCAGCUAACAAGAAUAUUUGAAACUUUGGGCACACCAACUGAGGAACAGUGGCCGGACAUGUGUAGUCUUCCAGAUUAUGUGACAUUUAAGAGUUUCCCUGGAAUACCUUUGCAUCACAUCUUCAGUGCAGCAGGAGACGACUUACUAGAUCUCAUACAAGGCUUAUUCUUAUUUAAUCCAUGUGCUCGAAUUACGGCCACACAGGCACUGAAAAUGAAGUAUUUCAGUAAUCGGCCAGGGCCAACACCUGGAUGUCAGCUGCCAAGACCAAACUGUCCAGUGGAAACCUUAAAGGAGCAAUCAAAUCCAGCUUUGGCAAUAAAAAGGAAAAGAACAGAGGCCUUAGAACAAGGAGGAUUGCCCAAGAAACUAAUUUUUUAAAGAGAACACUGGACAACAUUUUACUACUGAGGGAAAUAGCCAAAAAGGCAAAUAAUGGAAAAAUAGUAAACAUUAAGUAAAUGCUGUAGAAGUGAGUUUGUAAAUAUUCUACACAUGUAAAAUAUGUAAAACUAUGGGUUAUUUUUAUUAAAUGUAUUUUAAAAUAAAAAUUUAAUUCUGGUUUUUCUGAUUAGAGUGCAAAAGUGAGAAAAGUUCAAUACUCUUGAAAUGUAGAAUUGAAAAUGCAUUAGGGAAAACUUAAUAAAAAUUAUUACCAGUUAUUUGGAAGAUCUGA